ACAAAUAUUUACCGCCGCGCGGAGAGUGAGGGCCCAAGUCCGCCCUGCUCCGCCACUUAGGCCGCCCCAGACGCUUCCCUCGGGGCUGCCACCGGGUCGGGCGCGGCUGCCGCGGCUAGCGGGCCUUCCCCGCACCGGCGCGGCCCAACCGCCACCGAACCUUCUGGAAGCGGCGGCUGCCUGGGCCCCCACGCCGCCAGAAUCGUACGCCCGCGCGAGCUCUCUGCAGCCUUGGCGGCCUGGGAGGCGGGGCUCGGGGUGGGGCCGGCGCGGGGGCGGGGUCGGCGCGGGGAGGCCGCGUUCGAUUGCCCCCGGCGCGCAGGCCCCGCCUCACCAGCCCCAUCGCUCCACCUCUGCCCUCCCCCUUUAUGGCGCGGCCCGGGCUCAUUCAUUCCGCGCCGGGCCUGCCAGACACCUGCGCCCUUCUGCAGCCGCCCGCCGCAUCCGCCGCCGCAGCCCCCAGCAUGUCGGGCCCAGACGUCGAGACGCCGUCCGCCAUCCAGAUCUGCCGGAUCAUGCGGCCAGAUGAUGCCAACGUGGCCGGCAAUGUCCACGGGGGGACCAUCCUGAAGAUGAUCGAGGAGGCAGGCGCCAUCAUCAGCACCCGGCAUUGCAACAGCCAGAACGGGGAGCGCUGUGUGGCCGCCCUGGCUCGUGUCGAGCGCACCGACUUCCUGUCUCCCAUGUGCAUCGGUGAGGUGGCGCAUGUCAGCGCGGAGAUCACCUACACCUCCAAGCACUCUGUGGAGGUGCAGGUCAACGUGAUGUCCGAAAACAUCCUCACAGGUGCCAAAAAGCUGACCAAUAAGGCCACCCUGUGGUAUGUGCCCCUGUCGCUGAAGAAUGUGGACAAGGUCCUCGAGGUGCCUCCUGUUGUGUAUUCCCGGCAGGAGCAGGAGGAGGAGGGCCGGAAGCGGUAUGAAGCCCAGAAGCUGGAGCGCAUGGAGACCAAGUGGAGGAACGGGGACAUCGUCCAGCCAGUCCUCAACCCAGAGCCGAACACUGUCAGCUACAGCCAGUCCAGCUUGAUCCACCUGGUGGGGCCUUCAGACUGCACCCUGCACGGCUUUGUGCACGGAGGUGUGACCAUGAAGCUCAUGGAUGAGGUCGCCGGGAUCGUGGCUGCACGCCACUGCAAGACCAACAUCGUCACAGCUUCCGUGGACGCCAUUAAUUUUCAUGACAAGAUCAGAAAAGGCUGCGUCAUCACCAUCUCGGGACGCAUGACCUUCACGAGCAAUAAGUCCAUGGAGAUCGAGGUGUUGGUGGACGCCGACCCUGUUGUGGACAGCUCUCAGAAGCGCUACCGGGCCGCCAGUGCCUUCUUCACCUACGUGUCGCUGAGCCAGGAAGGCAGGUCGCUGCCUGUGCCCCAGCUGGUGCCCGAGACCGAGGACGAGAAGAAGCGCUUUGAGGAAGGCAAAGGGCGGUACCUGCAGAUGAAGGCGAAGCGACAGGGCCACGCGGAGCCUCAGCCCUAGACUCCCUCCUCCUGCCACUGGUGCCUCGAGUAGCCAUGGCAACGGGCCCAGUGUCCAGUCACUUAGAAGUUCCCCCCUUGGCCAAAAACCCAAUUCACAUUGAGAGCUGGUGUUGUCUGAAGUUUUCGUAUCACAGUGUUAACCUGUACUCUCUCCUGCAAACCUACACACCAAAGCUUUAUUUAUAUCAUUCCAGUAUCAAUGCUACACAGUGUUGUCCCGAGCGCCGGGAGGCGUUGGGCAGAAACCCUCGGGAAUGCUUCCGAGCACGCUGUAGGGUAUGGGAAGAACCCAGCACCACUAAUAAAGCUGCUGCUUGGCUGGA